GGAGAGGUGAUUGAUGUCCAGAACUUAGACAAUUUCUAGCAAGCGAAGGGAUUGAGCUCACAGAAGAAGAAAUGAAGGAGUUGAUGCCUCAUUUGACAUUUAACGGAAAUGGAAAGAUUAAUGUUAAUUCAAUAAUGGAGGGCCUGAAGAAGUUUAAACCAAAAGGAAUGGUGACUCUGCAUAAGUUGAAAACUGCAAAUGAUAUUAAAGACAGAGUCACUGGCCACAUGGCAGUUUCAGAAAUUAAACCAAAACUUAAGCUGAAUCCUCUAACAAAAGUACCCAUCUCCCACAAUAAAAGGGAUAGAGACUUACCAGGAUCUCUUCAAUGCCAAUUACAACACAAAGAAAAGAAGCUAAGUGCUUCACAAAUGGCAGCUUUCCAAGAUGCCUACAACUUCUUCUACAAGGACAAAACUGGCUGUAUUGAUUUCCAUGGACUGAUGUGCACUGUAGCUAAGCUGGGAAUGAAUCUGACCAAGCAUGAUGUCUAUAAUGAAUUGAAAUGUGCUGAUAUUGAUCGAGAUGGGAAGGUGAACUUCUCAGACUUUAUCAAGGUUCUAACAGAUAAGAAUCUCUUCCUCAAGGCAGUGGUUCCAGAAAAGGAGACCUGUUUAGAUUUGGCUGGCAACCCAGGAAUCCUAUUGUUUGAAAUCCUAUCAAGGCUUCUAGAGACUUCAGCCCUACCCAGAAAGUCUAUAAUAGAAAUAGUAAGCUAUUUCCAAAGAAAAUUCCAGCAUACUGGCCCAGGAAUGUUGUGGAGUCCCUACACUAUGGGCUAUGGAAAAAGGACACUUAAGCCAGACAUAUGCACACCUCCAAGCUCAAGCAUGGCUGCCUUUGCUAAUGCUGCCCGGAUUGCAAUAAUGAAAGAAAAGGAUUUAUUUAAAUUUCUUGAAGAGCUCAAGAGAUGCAAUUCCGGUUCAGAUAGCCCAUAUUCAAAAAUACCCAUCUUUCCAUUGUUCCCUAAUGUGGAUGGGGUGGUGAUGGGAAAGCCAUUCAAAGACAUGCAGAAAUUAGAGAUGCUAAGAAUAAAGGAGCCUUUGCAUUUCUUUGAGGAUUAUUUUUUCCAUAAAAGAGACUGGAAAACACAGGCAGCAAAUAUAAAGUCUAUGGACCCUGCCUCAGGUUAUUCAAAUAACAUCUUCACCAUUGAUCAAAUGCUCAAGAAAAAGCAGACUUGUACAGUGGCCGAUGCAACUGCUAUUAAACAACAUGUGAAGAGAGCUACUGAUACCUAUAAUUUAGGAAUUGCCCUUGAACACCGAAAAGAGAUGCUAAACCUCUGGCAGAAGAUCCGAGGGGAUUUGAUUGGGAUGGACUCUAGAAAUGAGUCCUUUUAUGACACCUUUUCUACUUAUACAUGGUCCUGGAAUGUUUGCCAAGAAUUACUUUCUCCUAAGGACUUAAGGUUAUAUGAUGCCUAUGUGAAUAGAAAUUCCUCCCAUAACUCCAGAUCCUCUUCCUCAUCAGAUACCAGUGAAUGUUACACAGACUCAGGAAGAAAAAGAAAACGGAAAGGUUUAAAGGGAUUUCAACAAUGAAAUUUCUACAUUUUCUAAACAGCUCAUCACAAACUACUUUUUCAUAGUUAUCAAAAUUAUUGUUUCUUGCUUUUGUCUAAGUACAUUCUUAGAAGCUGGAAAUUUUGACAUCUUUUGGAUUCUGACCAGUAAAAAAGUUUAAGUCAUAAAA